ACAGUUGGCGCCCACCGGCAUCAGCGUGAAGGGAGCUCCUCGCUGGCUGCCGACGGGGCUGCAGGGCUCGCUAGCCGCUCACCUGCGUGUGAGCGCGGAGCCCGCAGUACCCGCCGUCCGGGCUCAGAGGACGUGACUCCCCGACCCUGCGCCCGGCAGUCCCCGGGGGCCGUGCGCCCGGCCCAGGCUCGGAGGUCCAGCCCAGCGGCGGCUCAGGCUGCGCGCCUGGCUCCCAGCCUCAGUUUCCCCAUUGGUAAAGCAUUGACGGUGGUUGCGGACGGCUUCUGCGGACAGAGCCUUGGGCUCCGACGUCUGCGCGGGAGCCAAGCCGCCAUGGCCUACCACAGCUUCCUGGUGGAGCCCAUCAGCUGCCACGCCUGGAACAAGGACCGCACCCAGAUUGCCAUCUGCCCCAACAACCAUGAGGUGCAUAUCUAUGAAAAGAGCGGUGCCAAAUGGACCAAGGUGCACGAGCUCAAGGAGCACAACGGGCAGGUGACAGGCAUCGACUGGGCCCCCGAGAGUAACCGUAUUGUGACCUGCGGCACAGACCGCAACGCCUACGUGUGGACGCUGAAGGGCCGCACAUGGAAGCCCACGCUGGUCAUCCUGCGGAUCAACCGGGCUGCCCGCUGCGUGCGCUGGGCCCCCAACGAGAACAAGUUUGCUGUGGGCAGCGGCUCUCGUGUGAUCUCCAUCUGUUAUUUCGAGCAGGAGAAUGACUGGUGGGUUUGCAAGCACAUCAAGAAGCCCAUCCGCUCCACCGUCCUCAGCCUGGACUGGCACCCCAACAAUGUGCUGCUGGCUGCCGGCUCCUGUGACUUCAAGUGUCGGAUCUUUUCAGCCUACAUCAAGGAGGUGGAGGAACGGCCGGCACCCACCCCGUGGGGCUCCAAGAUGCCCUUUGGGGAACUGAUGUUCGAAUCCAGCAGUAGCUGCGGCUGGGUACAUGGCGUCUGUUUCUCAGCCAGCGGGAGCCGCGUGGCCUGGGUAAGCCACGACAGCACCGUCUGCCUGGCUGAUGCCGACAAGAAGAUGGCCGUCGCGACUCUGGCCUCUGAAACACUACCACUGCUGGCGCUGACCUUCAUCACAGACAACAGCCUGGUGGCAGCGGGCCACGACUGCUUCCCGGUGCUGUUCACCUAUGACGCCGCCGCGGGGAUGCUGAGCUUCGGCGGGCGGCUGGACGUUCCUAAGCAGAGCUCGCAGCGUGGCUUGACGGCCCGCGAGCGCUUCCAGAACCUGGACAAGAAGGCGAGCUCCGAGGGUGGCACGGCUGCGGGCGCGGGCCUAGACUCGCUGCACAAGAACAGCGUCAGCCAGAUCUCGGUGCUCAGCGGCGGCAAGGCCAAGUGCUCGCAGUUCUGCACCACUGGCAUGGAUGGCGGCAUGAGUAUCUGGGAUGUGAAGAGCUUGGAGUCAGCCUUGAAGGACCUCAAGAUCAAAUGACCUGUGAGGAAUAUGUUGCCUUCAUCCUAGCUGCUGGGGAAGCGGGGAGAGGGGUCAGGGAGGCUAAUGGUUGCUUUGCUGAAUGUUUCUGGGGUACCAAUACGAGUUCCCAUAGGGGCUGCUCCCUCAAAAAGGGAGGGGACAGAUGGGGAGCUUUUCUUACCUAUUCAAGGAAUACGUGCCUUUUUCUUAAAUGCUUUCAUUUAUUGAAAAAAAAAAAAAAUGCCCCCAAAGCACUAUGCUGGUCAUGAACUGCUUCAAAAUGUGGAGGUAAUAAAAUGCAACUGUGUAAAAAAAAAAAAAAAAAAAAAAGUAAUUAUGGACAUG